CAGGGGUUCACCAUGUUGGCCAGGCUAGUCUUGAACUCCUGACCUCAGGUGAUCUGCCUACCUCAGCCUCCCAGUGUGAGCCACCGCACCCAGCCUGGAUUGUUGAAUUCAAUGCUUGGGUCACCUCCAGAUUCAUUUUCACAGUCUUUCAUGUUUUGGUCAUAUUACAUUGUAUUUUGCUGCCAUAUGACUGAUCUCUUUUUGUUAAAUGUGAGAUACUCGUUAAAAAAUAUUUAGCAAUGAAUUGAGGCCUAGUGGCAUGUUAUCUUGCUGCAGAAGAGAUGGGAGUCUACUUCUGGGGGAUGGUCACGGGUCCUCCAUACAGGCUGCAAUUGAGGUCGUCGGUGCAGGCUCAGUCCCUACAAAGGCCAGGGUAUUUCCUGUCCACCUCUAUUCUGAUGCAUGACUCUUCUGGGUCUCAACCAGAGCCAGUGGACUUCAGUACGGGUCGCUUUCAUUGGCAGACCCUCAAUCCACUUGUUUUCCAUCUAAUCCCACGCAUGUGUGCAAAAGCUGCUGUGCUUCUUUGCAUCUCAGUAGUUCCUUCUGGAAUUCAGCAAUGAAACUCAGGGAAAUGGGUUCCAAAUGCGAGGCUGACUUUCGUCCUGGGUUUCCUUCUUCUCCAUCUUCACCUCAUGUCUGUUUACUGCCAUGUUAGCAAUUUGAUGUAUUCAAUCAUGGGUUUUAUAUUCUGUUUGGUGUCCCCCAUUGUUCUCAUCGGAGAUCAGAAGCUUCAGAUGCACUUAUGUCAACUCAAGAGUAGAAUGCUUCCUUAGCUUCCCUCCAGAGUCAGGUUUUGUGUUUCUAGUUCCCAAGUGGACAGCAGGAGUAGUGAUGUCCUCACUGGCUUCUCAUUUGCAUUAAGCUGUGAGCUUCUUUACCGUGGGGACAGGACCCUGCUCCCAUUGCAUUCUCAGCACCACACCACACACUCCUUGUUGGAGGCCACUCCAGACAGCAUGUGCUGAAGGAUGCCCUGUGGUCAGAAACAAGUUCAUUAACUUUCUCUUUGAAGUGUUUUCGCCCCUGUUUCCUAGCGUUCUGGGAAUUUUACACAUCCUUCCUAUAAAACCAAGUAUCAGGUGAGAUCCUUAGGAUCAGGACCAUGAAUCAAGUGGUGUGAGGGCAACACAGCAAACUUACCCUUUUUAGGCCAUUUCCUUUUUCUGCCCUCAAUGUCCGUGAAGUGAACCUUGUUAAAGUCAGUCAACACCAGGGUGGAUGGUUUGCCGUUGUCACCUAUUUUCAGGACAUAACACCCUGACUUAGGAGCCAUUCCGAUCAUUUCUAAUUCAAUAGAUGCGCCCAGCAUUCAGAUUGCCUUUUCUCUCAACCAGGAUCUUUAAAGUCGAUGACAAGAGUUCCAGUCCUGAAUCAUGGCAAAGUGCAGUAGUGAACUGCGGGGUUAAUGACACCAUAUUCUGGAAGGAUCUCUCUAUGGCUGAUGGUCUCAGUUCCGGCAUCAGCCUCUGACUGAGAAGCAGGUCUCACACAGGAAGAGUCAGAUGAGGAGCAAUCCUCUGCUUCCGAUGGAGUUAGUUGUGAUGAGUUGGUGAGGUCUGGUUUUUCACACUGAACUAAAAUGAUCUUUCGCUGUGUCAAGCACAAGACUGACCCCAGAGACACACAUAGUGCACCUCAUAGAAGCUUUUAAUAGUCUUUAUAUUUACUAAAGAAUAGGACUAACUAUGGAACUAUGAAGAUGAGCUGGAAAUGACAGGUGACUUGCCAGCAGGCCAGAGUGUGAUUUUUUUUGGUCCCUCAAUGGGAGGUGUCCAUUCUCCCUUCGGUUGUGAGAAUCAGUUGGUUCAUUUGUGGGAAGGUUGCAGGGGGGAUCUUUGAAUCACAGCCUUCAGAUGCCAGAAGGGCAGAGGGAAUCCCACAUGGACUGGUGGAUCAUGUGUGUGCAUUUCUCUCCCUUCUAACCUGAGGAAACUAAGCAUGAAAGAAUGUGAGCACGCAGAAAAGGAGAGGCAGGUAUCAGAGGCAGAGGAAAAUGGGAAAUUGGAUAUGAAAGAAAUACACACCUACAAGAAAAUGUUUCAACGUGCGCAAGAGUUGCGGCGGCGGGCAGAGGACUACCACAAAUGCAAAAUCCCCCCUUCUGCAAGAAAGCCUCUUUGCAACUGGGUAAGUUUGUUUGUUUUCCUUGCUUUUGAACAUAGUCUGCCAGGUCAGGACAUGGAUACAUUUUUCUCCCUACAGCUCUGUGCUCAAGCCCUGCAGAGGGAGAUGGCAGAGAGGAAGGCUGCCUACAGGCAUCACAGUCCCAUCCCUGUCAGAAUGGCGGCAGCGGAGCAUCGUCAUUCUUCAGGAUUGCCCUACUGGCUCUACCUCACAGCUGAAACUUUAAAAAACAGGAUGGGCCGCCAGCCACCUCCUCCAACUCAACAACAUUCUAUAACUGAUAACUCCCUGAGCCUCAAGACACCUCCUGAGUGUCUGCUCACUCCCCUUCCACCCUCAGUGGAUGAUAAUAUCAAGGAGUGUCCUCUUGCUCCUCUUCCACCCUCUCCUCUUCCACCCUCAGUGGAUGAUAAUCUGAAGGAAUGUCUCUUUGUCCCGCUUCCACCCUCUCCUCUUCCACCCUCAGUGGAUGAUAAUCUGAAGGAAUGUCUCUUUGUCCCGCUUCCACCCUCUCCUCUUCCACCCUCAGUGGAUGAUAAUCUCAAGACUCCUCCCUUAGCUACUCAGGAGGCCGAGGUGGAAAAACCACCCAAACCCAAGAGGUGGAGGGUGGAUGAGGUGGAACAAUCGCCCAAGCCCAAGAGGCAGAGGGAGGCCGAGGCACAACAAUUACCCAAACCCAAGAGGCGGAGGUUGAGUAAGCUGAGAACACGCCAUUGCACUCAAGCCUGGGCAAUAAGAAUAAAUCCGUAGGUCGAAAAAAAGAAAAAAAUCAAAAAACAAAACAAAACCCACGCUCCAAAAACAAACUAACGAAGAAUAAAUAAAUAAUAUAAAAAUAAAAUAAAUACUGCAGUCC